UGAACGCCCACUAAGAAGCUGAGACUGGUGCUGGGAAAGGUGUGAAGCGUGAGGGAGCAGAAGCAGGCUGGAAACGAGAUUUCACAUCACCCAUGUGUUAAUGAACCGGCUCCAUUGUCACCCACAGUCUAUUUUUACCUCCUUGCCACUUAGGUCUCACUCCAUGUUUAACACACCCAUCCCUUCUGAUCUUCACAUCAGCUUGUCCCCUGCCUUCCUGGGAAAGGCGGGUGUGGGGGUGGAGGCCGCGUGCCCUCGCCACCACCCAGCCUGACUUUCCGAGUGGACCGUGCCAUUCCCACCUCGUCAUGCCCACCCAUCCUGGAAACAUUUCUCAUGGCCACUGGGGUGCUUCUCGGGUGGUGGGCUGCCACAGGGGUCCAGAAUCCAAUGCUUCCUUCCCAGCAGACUCUCCCCUUCCCAAAGCUUGGCACCAGCACCACCCACUGGGCACCUGGCAGCUUAGGGCCCCACCCCUCUGAGCUCCUGGACCCUCAGAACUUGGAGUGGUGGCCUUGGAGCGGCUGUCCCUCCCUCUUCAGCCUUUCCUUCUAGACCCAGGGUCUGCCCUUCUGCCCCCAGCCCCACCUUUCCCUCCCCAGCUGACCCCUUGACCAGAUGUCUCUGGAGGAAGGGGUGGUGGCCCUUGGCUGUCACCGGGGAGGACACUCAGCCCCCUUGGUCUGUGAGCAGCAGGCUCAUGGGAGACAGCGUCCCGGGAGGAGGAGUGGCCAUUCCAGGUUCCAAGCAGCGUGGGAGUGUGUCCAACAAGCAGCGGGAGAUGGGAGGGCCAGUCACUGCCUCUGUCCCCACGAUUCUUGGUGUCCCUGAAGUCCCCCAUCUGGGAUCCUUCAGCUCCUGGGCCUCGGCACCACACUUCAGACUGCGCUCCCGGGAGGGAGGGAGGCCCUGGCUCCACGCCCUGCUGCGCCCAUUCCACCCUCAGCCACUCUGCUCGUGUCCACCCCCUCAUGCUGUCUGCCAUCGUUUCACCACUGCUCUUUGGGAUCCAAAUGGUUUCCACCGCGGCCCACCCCCACCCCAAGUGGGGGACAGGGCAAGGCGGGGACCAGGCCACCCCCAUUGCUCUCCCUACUCUGAAGCCACCAUGUUCCUCUGUCACGGUGUGUGUCCCCCGCCUCCUCUCUGCCUCUCCUGUUGGCCGCACGCUCCUCCCUGUCCCCUCGUCCACCCGGCAGCCUUCGCCCGUCUCUGACUAACUUUCUUGGCCUCUCUCUCCUUCUGUCUCCUUUCUCCCAUCUGCUCCUCACAGGGCUGCCCUGGGCCGGUGAUGGGCCCCUCGGCCUCUCCCUCUGCCUCUCUCUGUGCCUCUCACCUCUGUCUCUCUGUCCUGUGACCUCCGACAGCUUCAGUGGCGCUGACUAUCUUUCCCAGGCUGCUUGGCAGCUGUGCCGACGCUGCAGCGUGGCCAAAUAACUCUAACGUUCUCAUAUCUUCAGCAGUCAAUCUCACACUCUCCCUGCUCUUCCACUCUGUUUCUAACCUGACUUUACCUCUCCAGCUGUUUCGGGCUCCUUUCCUUCCCCCUGCCUGCCCGUGUGAGCACGUGUCCUCUCGUGUGUGUGUGUGUGUGUAUGUGGUGCGUGCGUGUCCACAUGUCCAUGUGUGCCAUGGCCCUCUGGGAGGGGCGCCCGCGUGUCGCUGGGUGGAGUGGGCGUUUCCGUGUUGUAGAGGCAGGGCCAGGUUGUCACAGCAGGUGUAUCGUGCUUCUGAUAAUCAGGAUGUUGGGCCCUGAAACCACUCCCUGCCCUUUCCGUUUCAGUUUGUCUCCCUUCACGUGCACACGUGGCAUGCCUGGGUCUCCCCAGUGCAUCUCCUCUCGGGAUCCCUGCGUGCCAUCGCUGUAUGUGUGUCGUCACUGCUGCUGUGGUUGGCCUGACUGUGGCCUCUGCCAUCCUCUCCCUGCCCCUCUGGAUGUCUGUGGGGCUCAUGUGCAUGUGUGUGUGUACAUAUGCACGCACGUGCGUGUGUGCGUGCGUGUGCGUGUGUGUAUGCGCAUGUGUGCGUGCGUGUGUACAUGUGUGUGCAUGCAUGUGCGUGUGUGUGUGCGCACGUGCACCCUGCUUUGGGAUCCUGAUGUCUCCCCUCCAGGGCCUGGCAUAUUCCAUGCAUGUCUGUCUGUGCCUGUCGUGGUCACCUGUGUGCUGGAGGCUGGUCUCUACCAGAGGGCCAUGGCUCAUGUCCACCCUCAGCGUGUGGCUCCCAGUUUGUGGCUGUGUGCUCUCAAAGCUGUUCUAUUUUAGCCUGUCCUGAGCCUCAUGCUACUGGUCCCCCGUCUCCUCCUCCCUACCUACCCCUACCUCUCUUCCUCCUCAUGGGACAUUCCAUCCUGGUCCCUGGGCAGGCUUUUAGUGCCCCCUUCCUGACCCCCAGCUGAACGGAGCCUGGGCUCACCACCCAGCCAUUGGGUCAAAGAACCCAGCAUCCUGGGAACGGCAUGGAGUCAGGUACAGACAGGGCUUCUCGGUGGUGCCCGUCUUUCUGUGACCCUGGGUGAGAGCCUUACCAAAUGCACAGUCUUCAGCAAGUGGGAGAAGGAUGGGAACUGAGGAGCAAGGGGGUGUAGGCUCACCCUAUCCAAUAUGGGGCCAUUAAACUAAAUGAGCUUACAUUCAACAAAAUUAAAAUUUCAGCUCUCAGCCACACUGGCCACAUUGCAAAUGCUCAAGUGCACACGUGUGGCAUGUGGCUGCUCCACUGGACAGCACAAAUACAGAACACUCUGUCACUGUGGAGAGUUGUCCUGACCUCACCUGGUCAGUCUCACGUCUGGAGGGUGGGAAGAGAACUCUUGAUGAGCCCAAGCAAACACAGGUGGGGCAUCUGGGAAACAGACAUUCUGGGCGUGUUUGCAGAGGGUAAUGACGCGGAGAGGCACCUGGACACACCACACCACGGUGGAGCCUCCCCCUUCCAGGCUGGGGGCGGAUGGGAUAGAACAAGCCUCUGAGGACUGGGGGCAGUGGCCACCUCAGAGACCGACUAUGCAAGCCAAUGACUGGAGGGUGGGGGGUUUCUGGGGAACAGGAAGAAUGGGGACACCCCCCAAAAUAUCCCCUAUAGGAGUAGUUAAGCCACAGUCGCCUGGGGUAGAGGCUGCAAGGAGAAUGGGCCCCGGGCAUGGGUCUCCAGGGAAAACCAGGUGUCCACGUGGACUGGAGUACCGCUCCUGCCGGCCCGCCGGGCAUGGCAGCUGCUGGGGUCUUCAGAGAAGGUUGCCUGCAGGAGGGAAGGCGGUGAACACAGCCCCCGUGCCAGGCCAGACACCCCACGAUGAGUCCGACCGCCGGACCGAGCCACGUUCCUCCGUCUCAGACCUCGUCAACUCCCUCACCAGCGAGAUGCUCAUGCUCUCCCCAGGCUCCGAGGAGGAUGAGGCCCACGAGGGUUGCAGCCGAGAGAACCUGGGCCGGAUCCAGUUCAGUGUCGGCUACAACUUCCAGGAGUCCACGCUCACCGUGAAGAUCAUGAAGGCCCAGGAGCUGCCGGCCAAGGACUUCAGCGGCACCAGCGACCCCUUCGUCAAGAUCUACCUGCUGCCCGACAAGAAGCACAAGCUGGAGACCAAGGUGAAGCGGAAGAACCUGAACCCCCACUGGAACGAGACCUUCCUCUUUGAAGGUUUUCCCUAUGAGAAGGUGGUGCAGAGGAUCCUCUACCUCCAAGUCCUGGACUAUGACCGCUUCAGCCGCAACGACCCCAUUGGGGAGGUGUCCAUCCCCCUUAACAAGGUGGACCUGACCCAGAUGCAGACCUUCUGGAAGGAUCUGAAGCCAUGCAGCGAUGGGAGUGGGAGCCGAGGGGAGCUGCUCUUGUCUCUCUGCUACAACCCCUCUGCCAACUCCAUCAUCGUGAACAUCAUCAAAGCCCGGAACCUCAAAGCCAUGGACAUCGGGGGCACAUCAGACCCCUACGUGAAGGUAUGGCUGAUGUACAAGGACAAGCGGGUGGAGAAGAAGAAGACGGUGACGAUGAAGAGGAACCUGAACCCCAUCUUCAAUGAGUCCUUCGCCUUCGAUAUCCCCACGGAGAAGCUGAGGGAGACGACCAUCAUCAUCACUGUCAUGGACAAGGACAAGCUCAGCCGCAAUGACGUCAUCGGCAAGAUCUACCUGUCCUGGAAGAGCGGGCCAGGGGAGGUGAAGCACUGGAAGGACAUGAUUGCCCGUCCCCGGCAGCCCGUGGCCCAGUGGCACCAGCUGAAGGCCUGAGUGGGGCCAAGGGAGGCCCAGGGGGCCGAGGGCCCAGGUCCCCAUCAUGCCCUCACCACUUUAUGCACAACGCCCGGCCUGAGCCCCCUGCCAUAGGGAGGGGAGGACCCUGAGGGCUCAGCCAGGGAGGGGUCCCAGGACUCAACUGGGCCCCGUUUCUAGGAAGUACCAGCCCCAUCCCCCACAGUCCAGCUCCGGGGAAGGGGCUCUGGGAGGCAUUUUCCUGCUUUGCCCCUUUUCUUCCUGACUUACUAAUACUAAAGAAGUUGGGGGAGCUCGAGAGCCAGACGGCCAGACAGGCAGACCCCUCCAGAGGCCCGCCAGGUGGGCAUGGUCCCCCAUUUUCUUUAAGGCAGCACCUGGAGUGGAGAGAGGCCACUCCCUCUCCAGCCCCCGAUGUGGACCCGGGGAGGGGAGGCUGAGGCGUUUGGCCCCGGCCUGGCCAGGAGAGGCCCAUCCCCAGGGCAGUUUCAGGUGCCGGCUGGGCCCUGAAUGUCGAGGAUAGUAUAUAGCCCGCUCCUGGGUCCUGGAGCUGUGGCCCUUUGUACUCGUGUUGUGUCCAUUGUGUGUGUGCGUGGGGACAGAGGCCUGGAAAUGCGGAGGACUAUACAGAGAAGGCAGGUUUUGUGAAGGCCAGGCAGGGUUGGAGGCCGGGGGUGUGAGAGGAGAGGCCCAUAGGGCUGAGUGGGGUCGGGUGAGGCAGAGGUCAGAAACAGAAGAGCUGCAGUUGCUGGAGCUGGGCUGAGAACUGGGCUGCCUCCUGCCAUCCCCCCGUCUCCUCCCCUUCUCCCCUUGGUGCCCCCCUCUGCUCAGAAUCUGAAGUAGUUCCCUCCUCAGCAAUUUCAUCUCUUGAACACUGACUCACACCUUUUAGGCACCUACUGUGUGCAUAGCAUUCCACCAGGACUCAUCUCCCUUCCUUCUCAGGGGGUCCCGAGCCCCGACUAGCUUUGCCCUAACUCCUUCAUCAAAAGACCCCCCGCCAGCUUCCCACACCUCAUACGCAGCCACAUCUGCCCUAUUCUCCAUGCUUUCCAGCUUGCCUGCCCUUCCUCAUCUCUCCCUGCCUGUGCAGACCUCCACCCUUCUUUCCUCCACCCCUCCAUCCCCCAAUGCUUGUAGACCUUCCAUUCAUUCCGUCUCAUCGUGCGUGGUCUCUGAUCGUCCAUCACCUGACCUUCUCCAGGACUGUCUUCUCACCCUUCCCCACUCCCUGGUCCCCGGGAGCAGCUCCUUCUGCCCGACUCACUCACAGUGCAGGGAAAGGAGGCAGGGAAAAGACCAGGAUUCUGUGAGUUCUGAGGUUGCCACACACAAAGAAGCUGUGGUUUCUCUGCCUCGGCCACUGAUGAGACUAAAACUGGCUUCCCCUUGGAGACGGCAGAUUUCAGGCUGAUCCCUGCUUAAGCCCUCUCAUCCCCACGCUGGUCCUGGUAUUGAUACAAGACCCAGCUGGUGACAAAGCCUCCAAUCCUGGGGGUCCACGAGCCUGGGCCUGACAUUCCCAGAACUACCGCCAGGUGGCGCCAGGCCCCCACAGUCUGUGGCCGUGGUCUUAGCCCCCAGUUCCACUCUGGAUGGGCCUGUGACACCCCAAAGAGAAGAAGGGGACUCUGGAUAGGGUCCCCACAUCCAGGGCGUGGGGAGACCAUUGGCAUUUGGGAACCAUUUUCCUUCGAACGGCUUCCCCUUGAGCUGAGCAUUCUGCUUGCUGCAGUAGACGGGUCGCCUUUUGCCCAUACCGAAAUUUUCUGAAAUUAAAUCGCACACCCCCACCAUUUCCUCUCCCUGGGAUCUGGAGGAACAUCAUACAUAGUAGGUGAAUCGUUUUGUAGAGUGAAGAAUGCUAAUGUAAAGCAAAUAGUCACCCACGUUCCUUGUAAAUCCAAAUGUUUCUAUAUUGUAGCUUUGCUUAAAAUGGGGUCGGCCCCAACUGCAUCCUCCUCUUUGGCGGGCUGGGGAGCGGCCCCCAGCCGGGACGGGAGGGCAGCGACCCCGAGGCCUCGUGGACGUGGGAGAGAGUGUGGUGGGAAGUCUUGAGCGGAGGAGGGGAUCUGCCCUUCUCCACUCCUCUCUUGGAUCCGCCUCGGUUUCCUGUCCCCCCACCACCCGCCUGCCCCGCGGAAGACCGCCCAGUGAGCCAGCCCCCACCUUCCAGGCGCCUUCGCCCUGGGGAUCCAACCAACUUGUAUCGAGUGGGCGGGGCAACGGCUCCCCAUUUUUCCCGAGCCCCGCCCACAGAGCUCUUAGCCAAUCCUAUGCAGAGAGCAUCUCCUGGCAGGGGUCUCUUCCCAACCAGACCCCACCCAGGCACAUUAGCGACCAGGCUUGGGCUUCCCCAGCGCCCCACCACCACCACGUGCAGGUGGAGCUCUGGGAUGCUAUGUUGGGGCGGCAAGCGGUGGGCCGAGGGCCGGGUAGGCUAGCACGGGAGGUAAGGGUGGUAUGGGAUGGGGCGGGGGCGGUCUAGGGCAAUAGGAGAGCAGAGAAUGGGGGAACUUGAGGGUGGGGGGAGGGCACCGGAGCCUUGCCACCAUCCCAGGACUUUGGGCAAGUCACCCGCACUCCCUGGGCCUCGGUUUCCCCAUCUGUAAAAUGAUGGUAAUAAUACUUCACCUACCUCAUAGGGGAGGUUGUGAGGCCACCAUCACCUGACCUGGGGGUCAAGGCAGGAGGACUCCGAAGGUGCUACCCGUGAGCAAAGUGUAAUUACCGAAUCCUGACUGCAAGGCCCACCUGCCCCUCCCCCACAGAGCCUCCAGAGCUAGCUGAGGCCAACGCAGGCCCAUCCGUCUCUUCACUCUGUCGCAGGCCCUUUCAUGGGCUUCGUCUGCCAUCUUUGUGGGUGCCCUAGACUUAGUCCUUAUCUUGUCCUGGUUUCCUUUCUUGUGACCAUCUCCCCAUGAAAGUGCUGUACAAAUUCCACCCGCCCCAGGACCCCCGCACCUGCCCUCUGGCACCAGAUGCCAGGGAAGGGACAGAGGAAAACAGCCACAAACAAGCCAGGGGGGCUCCCCGGAGCCCCAGGGGUGGGGAUUGGUGGCCACUGUUUGUAUGUUCUUGAGUGCAAGUGUUUUAUAAAAAAUAAAACAAAAACCCACCAUCACAAAAAAAAAAAUUUUGCAGCGAAGAGAAAUGAAGAAAAACUGAAGAAAAAAAAAAAACAGGAAAAAAAGAACCAUACAAAAUUUUUCCACCACACAUACCCUCUAAGCCAGCAAGAUUUCCUCUUUGCAAAAUCAUAUUUUUGUGGGAAUGGGCCCUGCUUUUUGUGGCAAGGCCUGUUCUGAUUAAUAAAGGAUCGUGAAAAAGUAGGGCCUUGGCUGUUUCCUCCGUGGGUCCCAGCCCUCCCUCACCUCCCUGGGGGCAGAGGCAGUGGGGUGAAGGGGAUGGGGGCCCCGGGGCUGAGCCUCCCCUCAGUGUGUCACCUUUGGGAUUUGACUUCACUGGUGACCAGGCCCUUCCCGAGUGUCCAGCCAUCCUCAGAUCUCUAUAGAAUAUGAUCCCACUGGCUUCCCAGAAAGCAGAGAGGCAGCUACAUCUCCCAGAUCAGGCCUGACACAAGGCUUUUUGGGAGUAGAGUCCUCUCUAGGCCUCAGGGGUGCCCUCCAGGGUCACCCAGCCUGACGUCCCCUCCCUCAGUUCCCAGAGGACACUUGCCACCCUCCAAGGCAGCUCAGACAAACCAAAGGGGGACGCUCCAGCUUUCCCACCACCAUCCAUGGGGCCACUGUAGUUUCAGGCCAGCGCCUCCUUCCUGGUCCCUGAGGUGGGAAAAGGAAAGACAAUGAGCUCUGUGUCUGUUGGCUGGACCUGCGGCUUCUCUCAGCCCUCUUCUAGUUUCAUUCUUUAGGAUUAGAAAAGUCUCUUCCACUCAAUAGAACAGGUUCCAGCCUGAGGUGUGGGAAGCUGGGUUGUAAUCCCUUCUGCAGCCUCUGUGGCCCUGGGCAAGCUCUUUCCUUCCACCUGUUUCUUCUGGCCACAACAAAGCAAUAACCAUCCCCAUCCCCUGCCCUUUCUUCCCCACCCAGCCCAGGGGAAGCUGAGCCCCCGCAGCUCUCAGGGUACUUCAGAAGGAAGGUGCUACAUCUGGUUCAGACACAGGCACAAAAGGAACGAGCACAUCCCCAUUGUCAUGUGUCCACCUGCUGGCCCCUGCCCCCACCAGGAGUGAAGCGGGCCAUCCCAUCCGCCCUCUGCUCCCAGCACUUGGGGCCAGCAGCUGCCUCCCGGAGCUGCACUAAGUACCCCAUCCAAAGCUGUCUGUCCCUCAUUUCCCACAACCUGGUUUAGAUAUCACUUCUGAUCUCUGUUCCAGAGAUCAGAGGAAGCCCCGGGGUCAGGUAAGUAGCCUCAGGGGCUCCCUUGGCCAGAGCUUCUGUUCAGGCGCUCUCCAUGAAAGCAGCCCUGGAAAACUGAGCCUGAAGUCAGAGACAGCUCAGGCCCAGCACAGGGGGCAGUCCCUUGCCACUGGCUCGGGCCCUUCCCUGGACUUUUUGCCUUCCUCCAUUUUUGCUUCUCUGGGUCUGUCUUCGUCCAUGCCUGCUCUGAGAUGCUCCCCCACCCCUCCCUGUACCUGGGACCACCGCCCUCUGGUGUUUUCUUUCUCCUGUGAGUCCCCCCCUGGAUACUGCUGCUUUCUGGAAGGCUGUCCUGGGUUACGUCCUGCGCUCCUCUCCCUCCCACGCAAAGACAACCAGAAGGACAAGCCUUGAGCACGCCGAUGCCCCAGCUCGUGGCUCCCCAGACCAUCUGUUUCCCGUGAAGACGCCCCGCUCCCCGUGUCUGUGUCCUGCGUGUAUGUGUCGUGUCUUGUGUAGAUUGUGAGCCCCCUGGGCAGGGAUCCCUGUCUGCAUACAUGUUCCAUGUGGCACGCCCAGGUGUGCUAAUAAACGUUCAUCUUCAGAACAAGA